AUGAGGACACAAAGGAAGGGAGACGGACAGACAGGGAGCAGCCUGCCAGUGGAAGCCUCGAUGGUCACCCCCUCCCCAGGAUAUUCAGUGCACACUGGAGAUCUCGAUGGUCACCCCCUCCCCAGGAUGGUCAGUGCACACCGGAGAUCUCGAUGGUCACCCCCUCCCCAGGAUGGUCAGUGCACACUGGAGAUCUCGAUGGUCACCCCCUCCCCAGGAUGGUCAGUGCACACCGGAGAUCUCGAUGGUCACCCCCUCCCCAGGAUGGUCAGUGCACACCGGAGAUCUCGAUGGUCAUCCCCUCCCCAGGAUGCUCAGUGCACACCGGAGAUCUCGAUGGUCACCCCCUCCCCAGGAUGCUCAGUGCACACCGGAGAUCUCGAUGGUCACCCCCUCCCCAGGAUGCUCAGUGCACACCGGAGAUCUCGAUGGUCACCCCCUCCCCAGGAUGGUCAGUGCACACCGGAGAUCUCGAUGGUCACCCCCUCCCCAGGAUGGUCAGUGCACACCGGAGAUCUCGAUGGUCACCCCCUCCCCAGGAUGCUCAGUGCACACCGGAGAUCUCGAUGGUCACCCCCUCCCCAGGAUGCUCAGUGCACACCGGAGAUCUCGAUGGUCACCCCCUCCCCAGGAUGGUCAGUGCACACCGGAGAUCUCGAUGGUCACCCCCUCCCCAGGAUGGUCAGUGCACACCGGAGAUCUCGAUGGUCACCCCCUCCCCAGGAUGGUCAGUGCACACCGGAGAUCUCGAUGGUCACCCCCUCCCCAGGAUGCUCAGUGCACACCGGAGAUCUCGAUGGUCACCCCCUCCCCAGGAUGCUCAGUGCACCGUGGAGAUCUCGAUGGUCACCCCCUCCCCAGGAUGGUCAGUGCACACCGGAGAUCUCGAUCGUCACCCCCUCCCCAGGAUGCUCAGUGCACACCGGAGAUCUCGAUGGUCACCCCCUCCCCAGGAUGCUCAGUGCACACCGGAGAUGUGGGGACCCUACCAAGAUGAGAUGA